AGCGGAGACCUCGCUGCGCUCAUGGCGUCGCCCGGGCAUUCAGAUUUGGGAGAAGUAGCCCCAGAAAUAAAAGCAUCAGAGAGACGAACAGCUGUGGCCAUUGCAGAUUUGGAAUGGAGAGAAAUGGAAGGAGAUGAUUGCGAGUUCCGUUAUGGAGAUGGUACAAAUGAGGCUCAGGACAAUGAUUUUCCAACAGGUGCUGUCCUGGAGCCGAGAGCUGCCUUGCGCUUGGCGCGCCCUGCACACCUCCCCGGUCUGCGCCAAGAACCGGGCGGCCCGAGUACGCGUAAGCAAGGGGGACAAGCCGGUGACCUACGAGGAGGCACACGCGCCGCACUACAUCGCCCACCGUAAAGGCUGGCUGUCGCUGCACACAGGUAACCUGGAUGGAGAGGACCAUGCCGCAGAGCGAACGGUGGAGGAUGUUUUCCUUCGCAAGUUCAUGUGGGGUACCUUCCCAGGCUGCCUGGCUGACCAGCUGGUUUUAAAGCGCCGGGGUAACCAGUUGGAGAUCUGUGCCGUGGUCCUGAGGCAGUUGUCUCCACACAAGUACUACUUCCUCGUGGGCUACAGUGAAACUUUGCUGUCCUACUUUUACAAAUGUCCUGUGCGACUCCACCUCCAAACUGUGCCCUCAAAGGUUGUGUAUAAGUACCUCUAGAACAAUCCCCUUUUUUCCAUCAAGCUGUAGCCUGCAGAGAAUGGAAACGUGGGAAAGGAAUGGUAUGUGGGGGAAAUGCAUCCCCUCAGAGGACUGAGGCAUAGUCUCUCAUCUGCUAUUGAAUAAAGACCUUCUAUCUUG